GGAGAAGUGCCUCAGGAGUCCUGACGCAGUGUCUUGGGCGCUAACGGCGGCGGCGGCCUUGUGUUUAGACUCCAGAACUCCCCACUUGCCGCGUUCUCGCCGCCGCAGGCUCCCGGGACGAUGGUGCCCCGCCUGCUGCUGCGCGCCUGGCCCCGGGGCCCCGCGGUUGGUCCGGGAGCCCCCAGUCGGCCCCUCAGCGCCGGCUCCGGGCCCGGCCAGUACCUGCAGCGCAGCAUCGUGCCCACCAUGCACUACCAGGACAGCCUGCCCAGGCUGCCUAUUCCCAAACUUGAAGACACCAUUAGGAGAUACCUCAGUGCACAGAAGCCUCUCUUGAAUGAUGGCCAGUUCAGGAAAACAGAACAAUUUUGCAAGAGUUUUGAAAAUGGGAUUGGAAAAGAACUGCAUGAGCAGCUGGUUGCUCUGGACAAACAGAAUAAACAUACAAGCUACAUUUCGGGACCCUGGUUUGAUAUGUACCUAUCUGCUCGAGACUCCGUUGUUCUGAACUUUAAUCCAUUUAUGGCUUUCAAUCCUGACCCAAAAUCUGAGUAUAAUGACCAGCUCACCCGGGCAACCAACAUGACUGUUUCUGCCAUCCGGUUUCUGAAGACACUCCGGGCUGGCCUUCUGGAGCCAGAAGUGUUCCACUUGAACCCUGCAAAAAGUGACACUAUCACCUUCAAGAGACUCAUACGCUUUGUGCCUUCCUCUCUGUCCUGGUAUGGGGCCUACCUGGUCAAUGCGUAUCCCCUGGAUAUGUCCCAGUAUUUUCGGCUUUUCAACUCAACUCGUUUACCCAAACCCAGUCGGGAUGAACUCUUCACUGAUGACAAGGCCAGACACCUCCUGGUCCUAAGGAAAGGAAAUUUUUAUAUCUUUGAUGUCCUGGAUCAAGAUGGGAACAUUGUGAGCCCCUCGGAAAUCCAGGCACAUCUGAAGUACAUUCUCUCAGACAGCAGCCCCGCCCCCGAGUUUCCCCUGGCAUACCUGACCAGUGAGAACCGAGACAUCUGGGCAGAGCUCAGGCAGAAGCUGAUGAGUAGUGGCAAUGAGGAGAGCCUGAGGAAAGUGGACUCGGCAGUGUUCUGUCUCUGCCUAGAUGACUUCCCCAUUAAGGACCUUGUCCACUUGUCCCACAAUAUGCUGCAUGGGGAUGGCACAAACCGCUGGUUUGAUAAAUCCUUUAACCUCAUUAUCGCCAAGGAUGGCUCUACUGCCGUCCACUUUGAGCACUCUUGGGGUGAUGGUGUGGCAGUGCUCAGAUUUUUUAAUGAAGUAUUUAAAGACAGCACUCAGACCCCUGCCGUCACUCCACAGAGCCAGCCAGCUACCACUGACUCUACUGUCACGGUGCAGAAACUCAACUUCGAGCUGACUGAUGCCUUAAAGACUGGCAUCACAGCUGCUAAGGAAAAGUUUGAUGCCACCAUGAAAACCCUCACUAUUGACUGCGUCCAGUUUCAGAGAGGAGGCAAAGAAUUCCUGAAGAAGCAAAAGCUGAGCCCUGACGCAGUUGCCCAGCUGGCAUUCCAGAUGGCCUUCCUGCGGCAGUACGGGCAGACAGUGGCCACCUACGAGUCCUGUAGCACUGCCGCAUUCAAGCACGGCCGCACUGAGACCAUCCGCCCGGCCUCCGUCUAUACAAAGAGGUGCUCUGAGGCCUUUGUCAGGGAGCCCUCCAGGCACAGUGCUGGUGAGCUUCAGCAGAUGAUGGUUGAGUGCUCCAAGUACCAUGGCCAGCUGACCAAAGAAGCAGCAAUGGGCCAGGGCUUUGACCGACACUUGUUUGCUCUGCGGCAUCUGGCAGCAGCCAAAGGGAUCAUCUUGCCUGAGCUCUACCUGGACCCUGCAUACGGGCAGAUAAACCACAAUGUCCUGUCCACGAGCACACUGAGCAGCCCAGCAGUGAACCUUGGGGGCUUUGCCCCUGUGGUCUCUGAUGGCUUUGGUGUUGGGUAUGCUGUUCAUGACAACUGGAUAGGCUGCAAUGUCUCUUCCUACCCAGGCCGCAAUGCCCGGGAGUUUCUCCAAUGUGUGGAGAAGGCCUUAGAAGACAUGUUUGAUGCCUUAGAAGGCAAAUCCAUCAAAAGUUAACUUCUGGGCAGAUGAAAAGCUACCAUCACUUCCUCAUCAUGAAAACUGGGAGGCCGGGCAUGGUGGCUCAUGCCUGUAAUCCCAGCAUUUUGAGAGGCUGAGGCGGGUGGAUCACUUGAGGUCAGGAGUUUGAGACCAACCUGGCCAACAUGGUGAAACCUUGUCUCUACUAAAAAUACAAAAAUUAGCUGGGUGUGGUGGCAUGUGCCUAUAAUCCCAGCUACUUGGGAGGUUGAAGCAGAAUUGCUUGAACCCAGGAGGUGGAGGUUGCAGUGAGCUGAGAUCACACCACUGCACUCCGGCCUGGGCGACAGAGCGAGACUGUCUCAAAAAAACAAAAAAGAAAAAAAAACUGGGGCCUGUGUAGCCAGUGGGUGCUAUUCUGUGAAACUAAUCAUAAGCUGCCUAGGCAGCCAGCUACAGGCUUGAGCUUUAAAUUCAUGGUUUUAAAGCUAAACGUAAUUUCCACUUGGGACUAGAUCACAACUGAAGAUAACAAGAGAUUUAAGUUUUAAGGGCAUUUAAUCAGGAGGAAAGGUUUGGAAAACUAACUCAGGUGUAUUUAUUGUUUAAGCAGAAAUAAAGUUUAAUUUUUGCUUGAA